UGGUGGGGAGGGGCUGGAAGCAGGAAUGGGGAGAGCAAGGGUGGGCACUCGAAGACUCCAGUGCCCGUCGGAUGACCUCAUGAAGGACAGGCACCAGCCUGGACGGUACCCCAGUUUGGAGCAUGGCCAGUGGCAGCUGGUGAUGCAUGAGCGUCAGGAAGUGAGGCUGCUUUGGGGGACACUAGUGACAUUGGUUUCCAUCUGUUGAAGGUGGUGUGAGGAUGUGCUGGGGUUGAUGGUGCUGGGGUUUGGGCAGGAGAAAUGGGUGCUUCAGUCUCAGGUGCAGGGUGAGGCACGACUGUGCUGGUCGGAUGUGACCUCAGGGUGCAGAGGGGCGGGUGGGGUCAUGUUCCCGUUUCACCUCUGCGGUGGACAGUAGACAGAUGGGCGCACAUGCAGGCCCUUGGAAAUUUGGUUGCAGCCAAGAGGGAAAGAGUCAUCCUGGCUUGAGGGCCGCAGGGCUUCACUAGCAGACCUGGGGACUCUCCAGGGACUGGGCAGAGCCGUGUCCUCUCAGGGCCAGCCUCUGGGUCACUGCUGAACCGCAGCAGGGAGCUGUCAAAGGCCUUUUGUCCUGGCCGGGUUGGCAAUCUGGCAGCCCACUGUGCCUCCUCUGCCUUGGGGAAGAAGAGUCCUUGACCACAGCUCUAGUCACUGCAUGGGGGUAGGGGGCCCGGGAGGAAGGGCGGGGUUGUUGGAUAGCCCCUUUUUUUUUUUGACAAGUGUGAGAAUUUUGUGUUACCAAGCUACAGGACAAAGGGCCCAGGCAUCUCUUCUGAGCGCCUUUCUCCCCAAAGAACAGUGUGAACUUUGCUGGCUCUGAGCCGGGCUGUGCUGCGUCCAAUUCCCAGGCUCUGCCCUGCUGCAUUGAGGAGACCCUGGGAGCCAAAGGCCCAGGAAGGGGUUUGGGGCUGGGUCCUGGCAGGGCCACCAGGGUCACCUGCUUCCAUGGUGGCAUGAGCCUCCCUGCUCAUGCAUGUCGCCACAUGUCAUGGAGCCCUGAGCCUCUGGGAGCCUUGGCUUCGAGAUGAAAAAGACGCCCCCAGCCCCUCUGUGCUGCAGGGUCUCCAUUCUGGAGCCAGACCUGAGGCUGCUCCUCAGGCCGAGACCCCUUAGCCGAGAUGUGCAGCUUGUCCCAGCCGCCAGCCCAGACCUCACAGAACUGUGCCCGGCGUAGGCAAAGUGGGCCAGGGCAAGAACUGCUCCCCUUGGGGGGCUCGCUUACCUUCCCCCCGGGGCUCCGGCAGGGCAGACAUCCCUCCUCGUAGGUUAGUGUCCUCCGGGCACGAUGGGGAGGCCUGAGACUAAGAGUUUCGUGGGCGGCUAGCCACCCAGGUGCCCAGGCAAGAGACCAAGGGCACGAGAUGUUCCAGUAUAAUAAAAUAUAUAAUACAACAAUAGUUAUACUAGAUAUAGGUCAUAGACAUGAUUAUAUAUGAAUAUCAUUCAUCAUUAGUUUGUAGCAAUUACUCUUUGUUCCCGUAUUAUAAUAAUCCUUGCUCUACAAUCAUAAUCUAGGAAAAACCAGGCCAUACAGAGAUAGGAGCUGAGGGGACAUAGUGAGAAGUGACCAGAAGACAAGUGUGAGCCUUCUGUCACGCCCAGACAGGGCCACCAGAGGGCUCCUUGGUCUAGCGGUGACACCAGCGUCUGGGAAGACGCCCGUUGCCAAGCGGACCGUGGUCUAGCGGUAGCCUCAGUGUCACGGAAAAACACCUGCUACUUAGCGGACUGGGAAAGGGAGUCUCCCUUUCCCCGGGGGAGUUUAGAGAAGACUCUACUCCUCCACCUCUUGUGGAGGACCUGACAUCAGUCAGGCCCGCCCGCAGUUAUCCGGAGGCCUAACCGUCUCCCUGUGAUGCUGUGCUUCAGUGGUCACGCUCCUAGUCCGCCUUCAUGUUCCAUCCUGUGCACCUGGCUCUGCCUUCUAGAUAACAGCAGCAAAUUAGUGAAAGUACUGAAAGUCUCUGAUAAGCAGAAAUAAUGGCGUAAGCUGUCUCUCUCUCUCUCUCUCCUCUCUCUCUGCCUCGGCUGCCAGGCAGGCAAGGGCCCCCUGGCCAGUGGACAUGUGACCCACGUGACCUUACCUGUCAUUGGAGAUGACUCACACUCCUUACCCUGCCCUUUUGUCUUGUAUCCAAUAAAUAUCAGCACAGCCUGGCAUUCAGGGCCACUACUGGUCUCUGCGUCUUGGUGGUAGUGGUCCCCCGGGCCCAGGUGUCUUUUGGCUGGGAUGGGGGAUGGGGGAUGGAGUGGCUGGGGUGGGGGAUAGGGCGGCUGGGGUGGGGGAUGGGGUGGGUUCCACAGCAUCUUCUCUUCUCUGGGUUGUGCUUCACCAGCACGUGGGAAGGAGCUGGUGACGGGUGGUGCCGAGUGCGCCAGUCCCUGCAGUUAGCGUCCUGGUCAUGGCUUUGCUCAGGUUUUCUUGGUCUCCUAAAUAUAAAAUACCAACUUUAUAUUCCUCAGGCACCUUUCCCUCCCCCCCUCAUUGGUUCUCUCUCGGCCCUGUGUAGAGGGCAGUUCAACAGAGUCCUGUAAUAUCCUGAAGUGGAGGGGAGGCUGCCUGCCUGCCAGAGAGCAGCCUCACCAGCCCUGUCCCCAAGGCCGAGAUGCAGGCAGCAGGCUGGGGCCUCGGCGUCCAGUACUCUUGUGAACCCGCGUCCGUCCCUCCCGGCCAUCCGACCCCCCCGAGUGGCGUUUUCUGGGCUGUGUGUCUGUCACCUGGCCCCACAGUUCGUGAUUUAGAGCAGCCCCUGGUGUUCCCAUUCUCCAGAUGAGGAAACUGGGGACAGAGGGGAUGGGGCCUACUCAAGGGAGGAACGCUCACCGGGGACAGACGGUGACACACGGGGACACAAGGGGGCCUGUCAGGCUCAUUUGGGGAUUCUUCUUGGAAGAGCCAAGCACACAGUAGAUGCUCAGUGCCUGCUCGGUGGUGGUCACAGAGCAGGAGUUACAGCCCUGGUGUCCUUCGUCAAACAAAGGUCGCCGCCCUGGAGAGGCAGGUGUUUGACUUCCUGGGCUACCAGUGGGCGCCCAUCCUGGCCAACUUUGUCCACAUCAUCAUCGUCAUCCUGGGACUCUUCGGCACCAUCCAGUACCGGCUGCGCUAUGUCAUGGUGUACACGCUGUGGGCAGCCGUCUGGGUCACCUGGAACGUCUUCAUCAUCUGCUUCUACCUGGAAGUCGGUGGCCUCUUAAAGGACAGCGAGCUACUGACCUUCAGCCUCUCCCGGCAUCGCUCCUGGUGGCGUGAGCGCUGGCCAGGCUGUCUGCAUGAGGAGGUGCCAGCAGUGGGCCUCGGGGCCCCCCAUGGCCAGGCCCUGGUGUCAGGUGCUGGCUGUGCCCUGGAGCCCAGCUAUGUGGAGGCCCUACACAGUUGCCUGCAGAUCCUGAUCGCGCUUCUGGGCUUUGUCUGUGGCUGCCAGGUGGUCAGCGUGUUUACGGAGGAAGAGGACAGCUUUGAUUUCAUUGGUGGAUUUGAUCCAUUUCCUCUCUACCAUGUCAAUGAAAAGCCAUCCAGUCUCUUGUCCAAGCAGGUGUACUUCCCCACAGGCCAGACCCCACUGAGAUGUCAGCAAACAGGCACAAGACGCUGACCUGCCGGCACAGAGAGAGGCAGUGGGGGCUUUCCAGAGCCUCAGUCCCACCCAUCUCCUUUCUGCCAAAGGCCUGAAGCCGUCCACUGCUUGGACUUUGUUCCAUUUCAGGUUCUCCAAGGGGAGGGGGUGGCAGCCCCCAGUGGCUGCCCCAGCCCUGUUCCCCCAGGUGCUCUCUGACCUUGUCCCCACAGGCCUGCGUAAGUGAGGAAACAGCUGAUCCUGCUCCUGUGGCCUCCAGCCUCAGCGACCGACCAGUGACAAUGACAGGAGCUCCCAGGCCUUGGGACGCGCCCCCACCCAGCACCCCCCAGGCGGCCGGCAGCACCUGCCCUGGGUUCUAAGUACUGGACACCAGCCAGGGCGGCAGGGCAGUGCCACGGCUGGCUGCAGCGUCAAGAGAGUUUGUAAUUUCCUUUCUCUUAAAAAAAAAAAAGAAAAGAAAACAUACAAAAGAAAAGGCAAAACCCCACAUGCCCACCUCCUCUGGCAACAUGGGGGUCACAGCUCUGCCCCCAGGCUGUCGUCUCGUCGAGGAGCCCCUCCCUCAGGUGCCCACCUGGGGCUGCUGGACCCUCGGGCUGCAAGCACUGCUGCUGGGAUGCAGCCUCCCCAGGAAGUCAAUGUGAGGCCCGAGACCCCUCAAGCGGUGAGGGCCCCUGUUGAACAUGGAGGGUUCCUAACCCCAAACUCGUGCCAGAAGAACCCCCACCCCACCCAGGAGCUGAGGCUGAUGGAGCCCUAGGGUGGGGGCUGGGCUUGACCAGGAACAGCAGAGCCAGGCCCCAAGGCAUAGGGCAGGGCACAUGGUGGUGACGAGCAGGCAGUACUCUUGUAAAGGGGGCUCUUGGGCAAACAGUCCCAAAGGCUCCCCCAGGUAUCAUCAAGUUGGUAAAUAAACAGGAACAUGGCCCUCA